GUCCUGGCGAGAAGCGAGCCGGCGGCCUGAGGAGGCGACUGACUGAGCAGCGCACCCGGGGAGCAAGGAGGCGCGGUGAACUGAGCGGCCCCUGAGCUGACAGAUACACUGCGCAGCUGGAACGGCGAGCGAGCCGACGGGCGAGUGAGGGGCGCAGCCAUGAUCACCUCGGCCGCUGGAAUUAUUUCUCUUCUGGAUGAAGAUGAACCACAGCUUAAGGAAUUUGCACUACACAAAUUGAAUGCAGUUGUUAAUGACUUCUGGGCAGAAAUUUCCGAGUCCGUAGACAAAAUAGAGGUUUUAUACGAAGAUGAAGGUUUCCGGAGUCGGCAGUUUGCAGCCUUAGUGGCAUCUAAAGUAUUUUAUCACCUGGGGGCUUUUGAGGAGUCUCUGAAUUAUGCUCUUGGAGCAGGGGACCUCUUCAAUGUCAAUGAUAACUCUGAAUAUGUGGAAACUAUUAUAGCAAAAUGCAUUGAUCACUACACCAAACAAUGUGUGGAAAAUGCAGAUUUGCCUGAAGGAGAAAAAAAACCAAUUGACCAGAGAUUGGAAGGCAUCGUAAAUAAAAUGUUCCAGCGAUGUCUAGAUGAUCACAAGUAUAAACAGGCUAUUGGCAUUGCUCUGGAGACACGAAGACUGGACGUCUUUGAAAAGACCAUACUGGAGUCGAAUGAUGUCCCAGGAAUGUUAGCUUAUAGCCUUAAGCUCUGCAUGUCUUUAAUGCAGAAUAAACAGUUUCGGAAUAAAGUACUAAGAGUUCUAGUUAAAAUCUACAUGAACUUGGAGAAACCUGAUUUCAUCAAUGUUUGUCAGUGCUUAAUUUUCUUAGAUGAUCCUCAGGCUGUGAGUGAUAUCUUAGAGAAACUGGUAAAGGAAGACAACCUCCUGAUGGCAUAUCAGAUUUGUUUUGAUUUGUAUGAAAGUGCUAGCCAGCAGUUUUUGUCAUCUGUAAUCCAGAAUCUUCGAACUGUUGGCACCCCUAUUGCUUCUGUGCCUGGAUCCACUAAUACGGGUACUGUUCCGGGAUCAGAGAAAGACAGUGACUCGAUGGAAACAGAAGAAAAGACAAGCAGUGCAUUUGUAGGAAAGACACCAGAAGCCAGUCCAGAGCCUAAGGACCAGACUUUGAAAAUGAUUAAAAUUUUAAGUGGUGAAAUGGCUAUUGAGUUACAUCUGCAGUUCUUAAUACGAAACAAUAAUACAGACCUCAUGAUUCUAAAAAACACAAAGGAUGCAGUACGGAAUUCUGUAUGUCAUACUGCAACCGUUAUAGCAAACUCUUUUAUGCACUGUGGGACAACCAGUGACCAGUUUCUUAGAGAUAAUUUGGAAUGGUUAGCCAGAGCCACUAACUGGGCAAAAUUUACUGCUACAGCCAGUUUGGGUGUAAUUCAUAAGGGUCAUGAAAAAGAAGCAUUACAGUUAAUGGCAACAUACCUUCCCAAGGAUACUUCUCCAGGAUCAGCCUAUCAGGAAGGUGGAGGUCUCUAUGCACUAGGUCUUAUUCAUGCCAAUCAUGGUGGUGAUAUAAUUGACUAUCUGCUUAAUCAGCUUAAGAACGCCAGCAAUGAUAUCGUUAGACACGGUGGCAGUCUGGGCCUUGGUUUGGCAGCCAUGGGAACUGCACGUCAAGAUGUUUAUGAUUUGCUAAAAACAAACCUUUAUCAGGAUGAUGCAGUAACAGGGGAAGCAGCUGGCCUGGCCCUAGGUUUGGUUAUGUUGGGCUCUAAAAAUGCUCAGGCUAUUGAGGACAUGGUUGGUUAUGCACAAGAAACUCAACAUGAGAAGAUUCUGCGUGGUCUUGCAGUUGGCAUAGCUUUAGUAAUGUAUGGGAGGAUGGAAGAGGCUGAUGCUCUCAUUGAAUCUCUCUGUCGUGACAAGGACCCAAUUCUUCGAAGGUCUGGAAUGUAUACUGUAGCCAUGGCUUAUUGUGGCUCUGGUAACAACAAAGCAAUUCGACGCCUGCUACAUGUUGCUGUAAGUGAUGUUAAUGAUGAUGUCAGGAGGGCAGCAGUAGAAUCACUUGGGUUCAUUCUAUUCAGAACCCCUGAACAAUCCCCUCGAACUUGGAAAUCCACAGUGGGCACCAAUGACUUACUGACUGCGCAGUUUCUUCACCUUCAUUUUCGAGGGUUCCCUCGCAAUCUGUUGCAGCGUUCCUCACGCGGGGGCACCACCUGCCGAGUCUGUCCUGCAGAUUCUGGCCAAGCAAUGGAUGAAAGAAGUUCUCAGACAUGGAUAUCCAGUGAAAGAGCAGGCUAGGGGGUUGCCGGCACUAGGGGCUGAAGAGAGUUAGCCACCCCGAUAAACCAGAGAUGCUUGCAUUUGUUUAGCACAGAUUUAAUGAGAAAGGCUUGGAGCAAACACAAUUUGUGGGUAAUUAACAUUGUUCACCCCCAAGUAGAGAGCAGUCCUGCACACGAGUGAUCAAAGGUUAGUGUCUGGAGACAGGAAUAAACAAAUUUAUCUAGAUAAGUUCCUUUACAUUCCCUUGUUAUCUAACCCUUGCUCUUAAGAGAAUUUAACUGCCUUUAGCUAAAUCCUCUUUUGAAGCUUUUGCAAAACCUCCCGGCCUUCCAGAAAGGUUUGCAUCUUUCCCUAUAAUUUUUAUAACUUUUCCCACCACCCUGACCGGUCUCCUACAAUCACUUCCAAGAUUAGGCUGUAGAAAAAAAUUAAUGAAAAGAAACAUAGUUGAAAUUACAACAAAGAAUUGGGAAUAUUUAGUAAAGUUAGUUGAUAGAGUAGCAGCAGAGUUAAGAGAGGAUUGACUACACUUUUGAAAGAAAUUCUGUUGUGGGUAGAAUAGCAUCAAACAGCAUCUUAUGCUACAGAGAAAUCUUUUGUGAAAGGAAAAGCUAAUGUGGCAGACUUCAUUGUCUUGUUUAAAGAAAUUGCCACACCCACCCCAGCUUUCAGCAACCACCACCCUGAUCAGUCAGAAGCCACCAACAUCAGGAGAAGACAUUCUACCAGCAUAAAGAUGAAUAUGCACUGAGGGCUCAGAUGGUCGGUGGCACUUUUUAGCUAUAAAGGUUGUUGGGUUGUUUGUUUUUUAAAUACAGAGGGUCUUCCUCUGCUGCCCAGGCUGGAGUGCAGUGGUGUGAUCAUUGCUCAGAGGCAAACCUGAGCUUAUGGAGCUUGGGUUGAGGCAAAACUGUAGAAUAGCAGAGACUACAGGCACUCACCACCAUGCCUGGCUAAUUUUGGUUUGUUUGUUUUGCAAAGACAGUGUCUCACUGUGUUGCCCAGGCUCAUCUUGACCUCUGGCCUUAGGAGAUCCUCCUGUUUCCACCUCCCAAAGUGCUGGGAUUACAGGCAUGAGCCACCCAUUGGGUCUGGCUAUGUUUUUUAACUGAGGUAUAUACAUUUUUUUGGACAUAAUGAUGUUGCACACUUAAUAGGCUAUAGUAUAGUGUAAACAUAACUUUUAUAUGCCCUGGGAAACCAAAAAGUUCGUGUGACUCACUUUACUGCUAUACUCUCUUUAUUGUAGUAGUCUAGAACCAAACCCACAAUACCUUGAGGUAUUUUAUUAAAGAAUAAAGUUAAAAUACAGUUGACCCUUGAACAAUACGGGAGUUAGCAUCACUGACCCCACAACUCUUACACUGUCGAAAAUUCACGUAUAACUUUUGACUCCCCCAAAACUUAGCUACUCAUAGCCUAUUAUUGAUCAGAAGCCUUAUGGAUAACAUACAUAGUCAAUUAACAUAUAAUUUUUAUGUUAUAUGUAUUAUAUACUAUAUUCUUACAGUAAGGUAAGCUAGAGAAAAGAAAAUGUUAUUAAGAAAAUCAUAAGGAAGAGAAAACACUCGUCUUCACUAUGAAGUGCAAGCGGAUCAUCAGAAAGGUCUUUACCCCAUUGUCCUCACAUUGGGUUGGUGGAGGAGGAAGAGGAGAGGUUGGUCUUGCUGUCUCAGUGGUGGAAGAGGUGGAGGAGGUAGAAGGGGAGGCAGAAGAAGUAGGUACACUCAGUGUAAUUUUUAGUGAAAAAAAAAUUGCAUAUUAGUGGGCCCACACAGUUCAAGCCCAUAUUGUUCAAGGCUCACUGUUAUAUGGAUACUGCCUGUUAUAGCUUAUUUGUUAUAUUUGUUAUAUUUGUUAUAGCUUAUUUAUUAUAUUUGUUAUAGCUUAUUUGUUAUGAAAUUACACAGUAAGUUGCUAAAGUGCAUGUUAGAUGAGUCAUACGUCUUAUGUCCUUUUAAACUUUAGAAGAGAUUUUCUACCCCAGGUUCCCUGGGAGUGAAUCUUUGUUAUAAAAAUUGUAUGCAAAUCCAACACAUAAUUUCUUGAACAUCCAUUAUGAACUAGGUACAGAGUCUUCUCCAUAAUAUCCCAGAUAGGAAGUCAUCCAUCUACAAACUGUAAAAUAUUUUUUUCCUAUCGUGGAUGGAAAUGUUGAAUAAAACAGAACAAAACACAGA